UGGGGGAGCAGAGGGCAGCACUUCCUCCAGCUCCAAAAGAGUGCACCCACCCCAACGUUACCAAUACACUCGUGCAGGCGGAAAGCUCCGACGCCGGUGUGCGUCUACGCUGGGGGCGUGGCCUGACUGCGCGGCCAGACGCCAGCGCCAUGGAGGAGUACGCUCGGGAGCCCUGCCCAUGGCGAAUUGUGGAUGAUUGCGGUGGAGCCUUCACUAUGGGUGUCAUCGGUGGCGGAGUCUUCCAGGCCAUCAAGGGUUUCCGCAAUGCCCCUGUUUGCAGAUUGCUGUCUGAAGCUCCCUUGUUUAUCUACUCUUGCUCAAGAUCUGUGUCUCCCACCGUUAAUGUGAGCUCUGAGAGGGCAGAGAGCAGACCUACCUUGUUCAUGGCUGUAUCCCUGCAUAUGGCAUGGUGCUUGGCACAUAUAGGAAUUCGGCACCGGUUGAGAGGUAGUGCCAAUGCUGUGAGGAUCCGAGCCCCCCAGAUUGGAGGUAGCUUCGCAGUGUGGGGGGGCCUGUUCUCCACCAUCGACUGUGGCCUGGUGCGGCUUCGGGGCAAGGAGGAUCCCUGGAACUCUAUCACCAGUGGAGCAUUGACCGGGGCUGUGCUGGCUGCCCGCAGUGGCCCACUGGCCAUGGUGGGCUCAGCAAUGAUGGGGGGCAUCCUGUUGGCCCUCAUUGAGGGCGUUGGCAUCCUCCUCACUCGCUACACAGCCCAGCAGUUCCGAAAUGCGCCCCCAUUCCUGGAGGACCCCAGCCAGCUGCCCCCUAAGGAUGGCACCCCGGCCCCAGGCUACCCCAGCUAUCAGCAGUACCACUGAGGAAGCCACUGCCACCAUGGGAGCUACUUCUCGGUUCCCUCCCCGAUGGUCUACCUCGAAGGGAGGGCUGGCUCCCAGUUAGCCCUGGGACCCUCCAGAGAGGGUUUCUACUCUGCUCCCUAGUCCCAGGGUGGGGGUGGGGCACCCCAGCUGCCCUGACAGAUGGGUCCCCUUUUUCUCUCUCAGGGCACCCCAGCCCCACACUCACAUGUACGAAGUUCUCACCCCAGCUCCUUUGUGUGGCACCCUGAUGAGUAUUUAAAGCCCGUUUUGAAAUGCCUA